GUUUUCCGAGGCGCGGCGGCGAGGACAGCGGCCCGGGGUGCGCCCCCUUUGUCUGUCCCCGGCCGGCGCCGCGUCCCCGCGCGCUUACCUGGUCUUGGAGGACAGGAAGGAGAAGAGAGAGAUUCGUGUUGACAAGUCCUUGUUGUCCAGACUCACACGGAUACAGCUGUGGGGAAGGAAGGAAGGCUGCAAUGCUGCUGUUUCCAUGAACAUGCCUGGCACCCUCCAGACUGGACUCUGAAACGGGCAUGUACAGAGAAGAGGAGACCCCAACACGCUUCAAGCUUUGAGUGGAGAGGACACAGCCUCUGCUGGGACAGGGAACAGAGGGAUGCGGAGACCCUGAAGAUGCUUUUGGACAGUGGUCUGAGGUUGGGACAGUGGCAGGAGAUACCAUUCACCCAGGAUCUCCAGGACAAGAGAUCAGCCUGGCAGUUACAUGUGUUUUUUUUCAAACUGGUUGCCAGGUUGGCAUGAGCGAUGACAUCAGAGAUUCCGACCUUCCUGAUUGGAGGGACCGGACUCUGUCGGCACCUGGGAGUUCAGUUGGACAACAGUAACUUCUCAGAGCUGUUCUCCACUCCUGACUUCUCCCAGCCUCGAGAAUUGAUAACACACUCUUCUGGAUCCCAGCAGUGUCCAGAAGAAGACCAAGGACAGAACAGAGACUAGGUUUGGUGAGAUGGGACAGAUUUUGGGAAAGAUCAUGAUGAGCCAUCAACCGCAGCCCCAGGAAGAGCGGAGCCCCCAGCGGAGCACCUCAGGGUACCCCCUCCAGGAGGUGGUGGAUGAUGAAGUGUUGGGACCAUCAGCCCCUGGGGUAGAUCCCAGCCCCCCACGUAGGUCCCUUGGCUGGAAAAGGAAGAGGGAAUGUUUGGAUGAAUCUGAUGAUGAGCCAGAGAAGGAGCUCGCCCCUGAGCCUGAGGAGACCUGGGUGGCGGAGACGCUGUGUGGCCUCAAGAUGAAGGCGAAGCGACGGCGAGUGUCGCUCGUGCUCCCUGAGUACUACGAGGCCUUCAACAGGCUGCUUGAGGAUCCUGUCAUUAAAAGACUCCUGGCCUGGGACAAAGAUCUGAGGGUGUCGGACAAGUAUCUCCUGGCUAUGGUCAUAGCGUAUUUCAGCCGGGCCGGCCUCCCCUCCUGGCAAUACCAACGCAUUCAUUUCUUCCUGGCUCUCUAUCUGGCCAAUGACAUGGAGGAGGACGACGAGGCCCCCAAACAAAACAUCUUCUACUUCCUGUACGAGGAGACCCGCUCUCAUAUACCCUUGCUCAGUGAGCUUUGGUUCCAGUUAUGCCGUUACAUGAACCCGAGGGCCAGGAAGAACUGCUCUCAGAUAGCCUUGUUCCGGAAGUAUCGGUUCCACUUCUUUUGUUCCAUGCGCUGCAGGGCUUGGGUUUCCCUGGAGGAGUUGGAAGAGAUCCAGGCUUAUGACCCAGAGCACUGGGUGUGGGCGCGAGAUCGCGCCCACCUUUCCUAGAGCUCCAGGGACCGUGGAGGCCUGAGGUCAUCGGCCUGAGAGAAGAACACCGGACCCAGGGGAGAUGUGGAUUUUCAGCAGGAACUUUAUUCCAAUGCUAAUGGCAGACAUCAGGAAGGAGGAGAGGAACCAUUUGUGCAGAUCAUCUAGAAGAACCUGGACCAUUCUUGACAGAGCUGAAUACAGUGAUCACGUUGUCCUCCAAGGAGCAGGGGUGGGGUGGGGUACUUCUAGGAGUCCUUGGAGAAAAGUAAGAAACCAGGAGUGUUUCCAGUUCCACCCUUUCCUGCGGCACCACCUCCCUUUUUAUAUUGCUGAAUGCCAACCUCCCUGGGGCGGAACCUGGAGGUCCUGUUUCUUAUGGACUUGGUUGCCACAGUCCAGGAGCAUUUGAAGGCACAGUGCAGGGGCUCAGAUUGGCACAGAAUUCUUUGUGAAAUAUGAGUGCCACAGACUGUAACAGAUAGCUUCAUGCACACUAUGCAUUUUAUUGGUUUGUUUGGAAAAUGUUGGCCAUUGAAUUAUUAAUAGGUUUAUUUCAAAUAGUUUGGAAAUUGUUGUACUUUUGAAAACAUGCUGUUCCUGUAGAGUUUUUUGAUGAGAGUUAUAGUUGUUAUAUAUACCUAAAGAUAAUUUUCUUUUCAUUUUUAAGUGAGAAUUCUUUUUAUCCUAAAUCUUUUAUUAUCUUUAAUUUUUUUUCUGUAUUAUUAUAUGUGCUCCUGAAGCGAGCACUCUUUUUAUCUAUGAUACUUCCAUAAUAAUCUCUUCUAUUUAUAGCUAUUGGUAGUUCCCCACCAGAAAAAAACAUAAUUCUGGUGAUAGAAAUUUUUAUUUGCUGUUUAGGUUUGUGACUGACUUGUGAGAAUUCAGUUGUGAUUUUUAACAUGUCUCAGAUAUAUAUACUAACACGUCUAAUAUAUACUAUCUAUUUUAUUGGUUUAUUUUGAAAAACAUGGGUAUAGAAUUAUUUAAAUAUUAUUUUAUUUACUGAAAUAUUUAUUAAAUAUAUUUAUUUAUUUAAAUAUUAUUAUUACUUUAAAUAUUAUUUUAAAUAUUUUGGAAAUACUGGUAUUUUUGAAUAGAUGCUGUUUCUAUAAAGCUGUGUGAUGGGUAUUAUAACUGUUGUAUACACAUACAUAUAAUUUUGUUUUCCUUUUUAAGAGAGGAUUCUUUUCAUCCUAAAUCUUUUACCUUUCAAUCUUUGUAUCUAUUAUUACACGUGCUGCUGAAGGGAGCAUGGUUUUUAUCUAUGAUACUUAGUUAACAUAUAUAUUACAUUUAUAGCUAUGUGGUAGUUCCCCUAAAUUCUUGUAAAAAUAAAUUUUUAUUUGAUAUUUAGUGUAUGUUUGAAAUGUGAGAAUUCAGAUGGAAUUUUUUAUCUUGUUUUGGCAUGUUUGUAUGUUACUUUAAAGAGGAUGUGUGUUCUAAAGGAGGACAUGAGCUGUGUGUUUUCAAGAGAACAGUGCAGUGCAUCUCUUGGGGAAACAUAAUAAAGAUGAACUUUUCUCACCUUC